GUUUAGUUCAGCGCAGCGACUCGGGGACCUGGAGCUGACGCCUAGUACGUAUGAGGAAGAACGGGGUGGGUGGCUGCCUGAGUCUGGAGGCGACGCCUCGGUUGUGCAGUCUGAACCUGCCCUUCUCAGCUGAGGGUGCUGACAGCAAGGGGUGGGAGGCGGGCCCCGAGUCCCCAGCUGUGGACACUUGUAUUAGCUUUAAUAGAAGAGAAAUGGAGGAGCCAUAGAAUAUUAAGGAUGAAUUCAGGAAGGCCUGAGACCAUGGAAAACUUGCCUGCUCUCUACACUAUUUUCCAAGGAGAGGUUGCUAUGGUGACAGACUAUGGGGCCUUUAUCAAAAUCCCAGGCUGUCGGAAGCAAGGUCUGGUCCAUCGAACUCAUAUGUCAUCCUGUCGGGUGGAUAAGCCCUCUGAGAUAGUAGAUGUUGGAGAUAAAGUGUGGGUGAAGCUUAUUGGCCGAGAGAUGAAAAAUGAUAGAAUAAAAGUAUCCCUCUCCAUGAAGGUUGUCAAUCAAGGGACUGGGAAAGACCUUGAUCCCAACAAUGUUAUCAUUGAGCAAGAAGAGAGGCGGAGGCGAUCCUUCCAGGAUUACACUGGGCAGAAGAUCACCCUUGAGGCUGUCUUGAACACUACCUGCAAGAAGUGUGGCUGUAAAGGCCACUUUGCAAAAGAUUGUUUCAUGCAACCAGGUGGGACUAAAUACUCUCUGAUACCUGAUGAGGAAGAGGAAAAGGAAGAGGCAAAGUCAGCAGAGUUUGAGAAGCCUGACCCUACAAGGAAUCCUUCUAGAAAAAGAAAGAAGGAGAAGAAGAAAAAGAAACAUAGAGAUAGGAAGUCAUCUGACUCUGACAGCUCAGACUCUGAGAGUGAUACAGGCAAGAGGGCAAGGCACACAUCAAAAGACAGCAAGGCAGCAAAGAAGAAGAAAAAGAAGAAGAAGCACAAGAAGAAGCACAAGGAGUGAGAGUAUAAAGAGUGUAGGGGGUGGUUGAGAGUAAGAAACCAGGAGCCUUGUGCCUUGAGACUCCUGGAAAGACUCAAUAGUGAGAAUAUAGCCUCCCACCCCAUUAACUUCGCUCCCAUGGGAGAUGGCUUCCCCUCAUGCAACAGGCAGGUUUGGGAGUUAGAGGUCAAAAGCAGCUGCCUGAAUGAGUUGUUGUUUCCUUAUCACUCCUGGUCCCUUUGCAAGUGAACCCUGCAGCUCACCCAUUCAUUCACCCAACUUCCUUCAUUCAGCAGGAGGUCCUAUUACCCUCUCCAGCUGCCACUGCCAGAGCUGGAUUCCUGUAAAGGAGUCCAGGCUAGAGCCACAGAGACUGUUGUGGAGGUGAGUUCGGCUGUAGUUAGAGUGAUUGGACCCUUCCUAUUGGUCUGUCCUGGGCCAACUGGUGGGUGAUCUCUGCUGCAUCCAACAUGGGAGCAGAGACUGGCAGCAGGAGGGGGGAACAUGGUGAGAAGUGGUGCUCACUUUUCCCAUUCCUCCUAACAUAGUUCUACUAUGCUAGAAGUGGCAUCCAGCGGCCACAGCUAGAAAACAGUCUGCAGUGUGACUUAACUUGUGUAUUGCAUUCCAGCAGACCACUGAACCAGACAGCGAAGCCAAGAUCAUUGUUCUACUUUGUAUUUACUACUGUGUGAAUCAGUUGAUUCUACUUCAGGUCCUUGCUUAAAUUCCUGUCACUAAAUGGAAAUGUGUUUGGUUUUAAA